AGAGGCUGUGUUGAGGCUAAUGGCGGUGCCCACGGAACUGGAUGGAGGGAGUGUUAAGGAGACCGCAGCGGAAGAGGAAUCGCGAGUUCUGGCACCUGGCGCCGCCCCGUUCGGAAAUUUUCCUCAUUAUUCUCGCUUCCACCCUCCGGAGCAACGGCUCCGCCUCCUGCCCCCGGAGCUGCUUCGACAGCUCUUUCCUGAGAGUCCCGAGAACGGGCCGAUUCUGGGGCUCGACGUGGGGUGUAACUCCGGGGAUCUGAGUGUGGCUCUAUACAAACACUUCCUCUCCCUACCUGACGGGGAAACCUGCUCAGAUGCCUCAAGAGAAUUCCGUCUCCUCUGCUGCGACAUAGAUCCAGUCCUGGUGAAGCGAGCCGAAAAAGAAUGUCCUUUUCCUGAUGCCUUGACUUUUAUCACCCUGGACUUCAUGAAUCAAAGGACCCGGAAGGUUCUCUUGAGCUCUUUCUUAAGCCAAUUUGGACGUUCAGUUUUUGACAUUGGCUUCUGCAUGUCAAUAACCAUGUGGAUUCAUCUGAAUCAUGGAGACCAUGGCCUAUGGGAGUUCCUGGCCCAUCUUUCCUCCCUCUGCCACUACCUCCUUGUGGAGCCCCAACCCUGGAAGUGUUACCGGGCAGCUGCAAGGCGUCUCCGAAAGCUGGGACUCCAUGAUUUUGACCACUUCCACUCCCUUGCCAUCCGAGGUGACAUGCCCAAUCAGAUUGUGCAGAUCUUGACCCAGGAUCAUGGCAUGGAAUUAAUAUGUUGCUUUGGCAACACCAGUUGGGACAGAAGCCUUCUGCUCUUCAGGGCAAAACAAACCAUAGAGACUCAUCCAAUCCCUGAAUCACUGAUAGAAAAAGGGAAAGAAAAGAACAGAUUAAGUUUCCAGAAGCAGUGAGAUGGGAGGGCAAGAAGACCAAGAAAGAUAUUGAAAGGGUUUUAUAUUGAGAAUUAUGUUCAUUCUCCUUAAUUCCUUAACAAUCAGGCAGCCGCAAAACCUGGCAGGAGCUUUUGGUAAAAUGUCCAAGGCACAUAAUUGAAAGAAUCAGUAUCUGUUCCCCAUUGUUUGGAACAAAUCUUGAGGAGAAUGAAUCUGUGGAGUGAUGAGCUAGGAUAUCUGGAUUGAGAUGGCCUAGGAAAAGUGGUCCUGGUUAUGGGUUAUGGAGAGGGCUGCUUUUGGGGAUUAUUUAUAAAGAUCAGACUAGGCUAGUCUUAAAAUAUGUCAGUUCCUGGGCUCUCUGAAUCCUACCUGGUUUCUUCAGGCUUCUGGACUUGCUAGGCCUGCCUUUGGGCAAAACCUUAGUAAUUCAGGUCUGGAAUGGGGCUUAGGAAUCUAUUUUCUGUUUUUUUGUUUGUUUGUUUUUGCAUUCUUCUAUUGUAAUAUAUACAUAAAAUUUACCAUUUUAACCGUUUUUAAGUACAGUUUUUCAGAACGUGGAAAUCCCAUCAAAAAUUGGAUUAAAAAAUUAAAAGAUAAAUUGAUAAUUUUUUUAAAAGUAUACAAUUUUGUGAUAUUAAGUACAUUUCACAAUGAGGCAUCUAUUUUUAACAGCUCCCCCAGAUGAUUCUGAGGCAAGCAGAGGUAGACCAUACUUUGAGUGCUUACGGUUCCAUUCAGUCCUUCUCUAUGUAUUUUUCCUGGGGUGAGUUCUUCCCUAUGGUUUUAACAACUACCUACAUGCGGCCGGGCGCGGUGGCUCACGCCUGUAAUCGCAGCACUUUGGGAGGCCGAGGCGGGUGGAUCACGAGGUCAGGAGAUCGAGACCAUCCCGGCUAAAACGGUGAAACCCCGUCUCUACUAAAAAUACAAAAAAUUAGCCGGGCGUAGUGGCGGGCGCCUGUAGUCCCAGCUACUUGGGAGGCUGAGGCAGGAGAAUGGCGUGAACCCGGGAGGCGGAGCUUGCAGUGAGCCGAGAUCCCGCCACUGCACUCCAGCCUGGGCGACAGAGCGAGACUCCGUCUCAAAAAAAAAAAAAAAAAAAACAAAAAAAAAAACAACUACCUACAUGCUUAUGGUCCCCAAAUAUAUUGGUAGCCCGACAUCCACAGUUCCAGACUAGCAUUUUUCCUGUUUUGUCAUUAUAUCCCUUAGUUCUUAGGUACAUCAGAAUCAACAGAUCUCAAAAGCAAGCUCACUACCCUCAUUCAAAACCUAGUCCUAUCUCAUUUGAUAGUAAUCAUUGCUUAUGCUAGAAACCUCAGUUGAUUUUCUCACUUACACUCCCCCACAUUGAAAUGCUCUCAAAGUCCAGCAGCAAAUUCUAUCAAUUACAUGUAAGUUUCAUUCCAUACAUGUGUCCGGUGCCUGGUGGGAGGUUCCUAUAUUAAAGUCAUCUACCUUCCAUCCAUUGUCUGCCUUACAGCCACAGUUUACUCAUCUGUACAACGAAAUAACACCACUUUCCUUUUCCUAUGCCCAAAUGAGCUAAGGAUGUGAAGGUAUUUUGCAGAAUAUAGAGUGAUAAAGAAAAAUAAGGUGCUAUUACACUGUGUGAGCAUGCCGCAGACCACAACUGCACUUGUUAGACUGGAGGCUUAUGAGAAAAACAUCUCACCUUGUAGAAAACAUGCAUCUUACUAUCUCUGAUAACUUGUUUUUCAGGAUGAUGAAGUAAUAAGGAGUCCAGCUUCAGUGCUACAGAGCAUUUUAAAGGAAGCAGUGUUGGGAGGGAGGGAUAUGGAACUAAUGGAAAUGAGGCUAGUUUAUGAUGGUCUCAGUUAUCACAGUAGAUACAGAGCUGAGUUUACCCACAAGAUCUUAAUUUAGGAACACUUUGAAACCCUGUAACCCUGCUGGGUGCUCUCUCCUCUCACUCCACCAAGGCAGCGCACAGAAACAUACAUGGGGCUGUGGUAGGAUGAAUAAUGGUCCCCCAAGAUGUCCACCUCCUUUAGCAAAAGGGGCUUUGCAAAUGAGAUUGAGGAUCUUCAGAUAGGGAGAUUAAUCUGGAUGAUCAGAAUAUACCCUAAGUGCAAUCAUCAGUGUUCUUAUAAUAGGGAGGCAGAGGGAGAGCUGACCACAGUAGGAGAUGUAAUGACAAAAGCAAGAGGUUGGAGUGAUAUGAAGAAGGGCUGCAAGUCAAGGAAUGCAGGUGGCUUCUAGAAGUUAGAAAAAGCAAGAAAAUGUAUUCUCCCCUGAAGCCUCCAGAAGGAACAGCCCUGCCAACACCUUGAUUUCAGAUUUAAUCUCCAGAGCUGUAAGAGAAUAAAUCAGUAUUUUAAACCA